CAGAGUUCUCCGGGGUGCUGCACCAGUGUCACAUUUUGGCCUCUGAGAUGGUCCAUUUCAUUCAUCAGAUGCAGUAUUACAUCACAUUUGAGGUGCUUGAAUGUUCUUGGGAUGAGCUUUGGAACAAAGUCCAGCAGGCCCAGGAUUUGGAUCACAUCAUUGCUGCACACGAGGUGUUCUUAGACACCAUCAUCUCCCGCUGCCUGCUGGACAGUGACUCCAGGGCACUUUUAAAUCAACUUAGAGCUGUGUUUGAUCAAAUUAUUGAACUUCAGAAUGCUCAAGAUGCAAUAUACAGAGCUGCUCUGGAAGAAUUGCAGAGACGAUUACAGUUUGAAGAGAAAAAGAAACAGCGUGAAAUUGAGGGCCAGUGGGGAGUGACGGCAGCAGAGGAAGAGGAGGAAAAUAAGAGGAUUGGAGAAUUUAAAGAAUCUAUACCAAAAAUGUGCUCACAGUUGCGAAUAUUGACCCAUUUCUACCAGGGUAUCGUGCAGCAGUUUUUGGUGUUACUGACGACCAGCUCUGACGAGAGUCUUCGGUUUCUUAGCUUCAGGCUGGACUUCAACGAGCAUUACAAAGCCAGGGAGCCCAGGCUCCGUGUGUCUCUGGGUACCAGGGGGCGGCGCAGCUCCCACACGUGAAGCUCGCGGUCCUCCCAGGGAGCUGCGGGUGAUGUUCGUUGCACUGCUAGACACGAAAUUCCCAUUGACGUCCUGCAGGAACUGCAUGCUGCAGGUGUCCUGCCCUUCCGCCCACGAGUGCGCCAUGUUUCAGCGGAGCGGCGUGUGGGAGAAGCCACGUCGUGUUUCACAUGUCGGAGUCGAAUGCAUUUGUAAAUCCCUAAGUCAAGUAGGCUGGCUGCACUGUUCACAUUUGUCUCUAAAAGUCUUCAUCGCUAAAAGAUACCAUAAUUUGCUGAGGCUUCUUAAGCUUUCUAUGUUAUAAUUUAUAUUUGUCACUUUAAAAAAUCCAUUUCUUUUAGAAAAAAUUAGGGUGAUAGGAUAUUCAUUAGUUAAGAUGGUAACGUCAUUGCUAUUUUUUUAACAUCCUCUUUAGAGGUAAUUUUUGUUAACAUAACCAAAAAUUAAAUUGAAACAAAAUGUCCCAACUAAGAAAAUAUAUAGAGCAUUUUAUUUUUUUUUAGUGUUGUAAAAUAUUAACCUCUGUGAGAUCCUUUGUAUCUUAAUGCAUUACCUUUACACAUAUUUAUUCUUAUUUUCUCUCCUUUCAGAGUUUACAUUUUUAUAUUUAAUUUACUAUUUCAGAUUUUUAAAAUAGUAUAGAAAAAAGUAGGAGUGAUAGAGAACAAAAAUACUCUUAUACAGUGCAACCCAAAUACCGCGAAUGCAUCAGCUAAAGCAGCGUGUAAAUAGGAGUGACGAGAAAGUUAAUGGAGUAUUUUAUUUUCAAAGUUCCUGAUAAGCAUUGGAAAGAAAUCGACAUGGAUAAUGAAGAUUUCCUUUUUCCUUGCCUAUUUUUUCAUUGUAAAUAUUUAUAUACUACUGACCAAGAUGUUGGGGUGGGGGGGAUUGUUUUUUGUAAAAAUGUCAUUAUCAGGUCACAUAAAUCUGCCUUUAUGUUGCAUAAGUGAAAAUUUAGAAAAUUAAAAGCAAUUAUCUUUCA